UAAUACAACAAAGAGCAAUAUUAAGAGCUAAUGAUUAACAAUGUUUAUACUAAUUAUUGAUAAUAUCCAUGAUCAUCUCUAUAUCUAAUUUGUAUUAUAACUAUUCUUAUUCUAACUAUUUUCUUUAUUAUACUGAAACAGUUUGUGCCUUCAGUCUCUUGUCUCAGCACCUAGGUAAUCCUUCACCCACACAUCUCCAUAUUUUUCUGCUGCCUGAAGAACUGCCUGCUUUUCAGCAGCGGUGAGAGUCUGACUUAGGAGCAACACGUGAGAUCAAACACCUGAGUUAAAUUUUGGAAAGUUUCUAUAUAUCUAUCGGGGUCGUCAGAAAAUCGGCUUGUCUCCCUUUAUUUGCUUAAGAUCCUGUAAUGAGAAGGGAACAUGAAGCUUCAUAGCACCAUUUCCAUCAGGCAUUUCCUGCAGAGAGUAGACCACAAACUCCAAGCGUUAGAAACACAGUUCAAAGAACUAGACUUCACCAAGGAUAACCUGAUGCAGAAAUUCGAACAUCAUAGUAAGGCUUUGGCAAGCCAAGCAGCCCAAGAUGAGAUGUGGACAGCAGUUCGGGCACUCCAGCUCACUUCAAUGGAAUUGAAUAUUUUAUACAGCUACGUCAUUGAAGUACUUAUCUGCUUGCAUACUCGUGUGCUUGAGAAGCUGCCAGACCUGGUGAGAGGUCUUCCAACCUUAGCCUCUGUACUCAGAAGAAAAGUUAAGAACAAGCGCGUUAGAGUUGUAUGGGAGUCCAUACUGGAGGAGUGUGGGCUGCAAGAAGGAGACAUCACAGCACUUUGUACCUUCUUUAUUGCACGUGGUAACAAGGCAGAACACUAUACUGCUAAAGUGAGGCAGAUGUACAUCAGGGAUGUCACGUUCCUAAUUACUAACAUGGUAAAGAACCAGGCUCUGCAGGACAGUUUGCUGAGGGCUGUGCAGGUAAUUGAGAAGGGGAAAGCAGUUAGGACCCCUGAAAAGCAAAAGUCAUCCCUCGAAGAGUUGAUACCAUCUGUCAAAAACUAACCUGUUACCCUAUGACCCAGUGAUUCCACCUACAGUAAUUUAUCUUGGAAACAGCAAAAAGUAUGCACAAUUUAUUAUAGUCUUAUUUUUAUAGCAAAGAGUGAGAGGAUGUUAAAUAAAUUAUGACAAAUUGAUACAAUAGAUACUUUCUUUGCAGCCAUAUAAAAGAAUGAAGAAGCUCUUUGUGUAAUGAUAUGAAGUGAUCACCAAAUGUAUUGUUGUUUUCAAAUGUUUAUUUCCAAUAUACAUUGCUAAGUGGAAAAAAGGUGACAAAUAUAUAUAUAUAAAUAUAUAUAUAACACAUAUUAGUUUACAUAUCCAUAAACUUCUUCUGCAGAGAUACACAAGACAGUGAUAACAUUAGUUGUCAGGAAAGAAAGCUAAGAGGCUAGGGGUCAAAGACAAGAGGAAGUCUUUUCACUGUUAAUCCAUUUUUUACAUUUUCAAUUUUGAACCAUGUGAAUGUAUUACCUAUUUAAAAAAUAAACAAGGCCGGACAUGGUGGCUCAUGCCUAUAAUCCAAGCACCUUAGGAGGCCAAGGUAGGAGGAUCACUUGAGCUCAGGGGUUUCAGACCAGCCUGGGCAACACAGUGAUAGCAAUAGGAGGCAGGUAAAUUCCUAGGCAGACAGGGAGGGGUCCCUGGUGAAACUCAACCUUCAAGCCAAGGACAGUCUAAAGCCUGAAAACCAAGCUAUGAGUUCUGGAUAAAUCCAUGAGCCAGACUGAGAGCUCCCAUUCUCGUCUGGCACCCUCUCUCCUGAUUGGUCCUUACCCUUCACCUAUUUUAUACAUACCUACCCUUCCGCGAUUGGUCCUCUACACUAUCGUGCCUAUUUCUGAAUGGUGCUUUGUCAAGCAUAGCCACAGACCAAUCAGCAUGCACUUGCCCAUUUCUAGCCCACAAAAACCCAUAGACUCAGGCUCGUGGCCAGCAACCCACCUUCGGGUCCCCUCUCACUGCCAAGAGCCGUUCUGUCACUCAAUAAAUUCUACUUUGCCUUACUCA